AUUUGUGACUUGUCUCAUGAACGUGAUGGGUUUUAACACAGACCGCUUAGCAUGGACUAGAAAUUUUGACUUUGAAGGAUCACUUUCCCCUGUCAUUGCACCCAAAAAAGCAAGGCCUUCUGAGACUGGAUCUGAUGAUAAGUUGAGAGGAUUCUAUUUUGCAAAGCUGUAUUAUGAAGCUAAAGAAUAUGAUCUUGCUAAAAAAUACGUAUGUACUUACCUUAGUGUGCAAGAGAGGGAUCCCAGAGCUCACAGAUUUCUGGGUCUUCUUUAUGAAUUGGAAGAAAACACAGAGAAAGCCGUUGAAUGUUACAGGCGUUCACUGGAAUUAAACCCACCACAAAAAGAUCUUGUGUUGAAGAUUGCAGAAUUGCUUUGUAAAAAUGAUGUUACUGAUGGAAGAGCAAAAUACUGGGUUGAAAGGGCAGCGAAACUUUUCCCAGGAAGUCCUGCAAUUUAUAAACUAAAGGAACAUCUUCUAGAUUGUGAAGGUGAAGAUGGAUGGAAUAAACUUUUUGACUGGAUUCAGUCAGAACUUUAUGUAAGACCUGAUGACGUCCAUAUGAACAUCCGGCUAGUGGAGUUGUAUCGCUCAAAUAAAAGAUUGAAGGAUGCUGUGGCCCGCUGCCAUGAGGCAGAGAGGAACAUAGCUUUGCGUUCAAGUUUAGAGUGGAAUUCGUGUGUUGUACAGACCCUUAAGGAAUAUCUGGAGUCUUUACAGUGUUUGGAGUCUGAUAAAAGUGACUGGCGAGCAACCAAUACAGACUUACUGCUGGCCUAUGCUAAUCUUAUGCUUCUUACGCUUUCCACUAGAGAUGUGCAGGAAAGUAGAGAAUUACUGGAAAGUUUUGAUAGUGCUCUUCAGUCUGCAAAAUCUUCUUUGGGUGGAAAUGAUGAACUGUCAGCUACUUUCUUAGAAAUGAAAGGACAUUUCUACAUGCAUGCUGGUUCUCUGCUCUUGAAGAUGGGUCAGCAUGGUAAUAAUGUUCAAUGGCAAGCUCUUUCUGAGCUGGCUGCAUUGUGCUAUGUCAUAGCAUUUCAGGUUCCAAGACCAAAGAUUAAAUUAAUAAAAGGUGAAGCUGGACAAAAUCUGCUGGAAAUGAUGGCCUGUGACCGACUGAGCCAAUCAGGGCAUAUGUUGCUAAACUUAAGUCGUGGCAAGCAAGAUUUUUUAAAAGAGGUUGUUGAAACUUUUGCCAACAAAAGCGGGCAGUCUGUGUUAUAUAAUGCUCUGUUUUCUAGUCAGUCAUCUAAGGAUACAUCUUUUCUUGGUAGCGAUGAUAUUGGAAACAUUGAUGUACAAGAACCAGAGCUUGAAGAUUUGGCUAGAUACGAUGUUGGUGCUAUUCAAGCACAUAAUGGUAGUCUUCAGCACCUUACUUGGCUUGGCUUACAGUGGAAUUCAUUGCCUGCUUUACCUGGAAUCCGAAAAUGGCUAAAACAGCUUUUCCAUCAUUUGCCCCAGGAAACCUCAAGGCUUGAAACAAAUGCACCUGAAUCAAUAUGUAUUUUAGAUCUUGAAGUAUUUCUCCUUGGAGUAGUAUAUACCAGCCACUUACAAUUAAAGGAGAAAUGUAAUUCUCACCACAGCUCCUAUCAGCCGUUAUGCCUGCCCCUUCCUGUGUGUAAACGGCUUUGUACAGAGAGACAAAAAUCUUGGUGGGAUGCGGUUUGUACUCUGAUUCACAGAAAAGCAGUACCUGGAAACUCAGCAGAAUUGAGACUUGUAGUUCAGCAUGAAAUAAACACUCUAAGAGCCCAGGAAAAACAUGGCCUUCAACCUGCUCUGCUUGUACAUUGGGCAAAAUGCCUUCAGAAAAUGGGCAGGGGUCUUAAUUCUUCUUAUGAUCAACAAGAAUACAUAGGGAGAAGUGUUCAUUAUUGGAAGAAAGUUUUGCCAUUGUUGAAGAUAAUAAAGAAGAACAGUAUUCCUGAACCUAUUGAUCCUCUGUUUAAACAUUUUCAUAGUGUAGACAUUCAGGCAUCAGAAAUUGUUGAGUAUGAAGAAGAUGCACACAUAACUUUUGCUAUAUUGGAUGCAGUACAUGGAAAUAUAGAAGAUGCUGUGACUGCUUUUGAAUCUAUAAAAAGUGUUGUUUCUUAUUGGAAUCUUGCACUGAUUUUUCACAGGAAAGCAGAAGACAUUGAAAAUGAUGCCGUUUUUCCUGAAGAACAAGAAGAAUGCAAAAAUUAUCUGAGAAAGACCAGGGACUACCUAAUAAAGAUUAUAGAUGACAGUGAUUCAAAUCUUUCAGUGGUCAAGAAAUUGCCUGUGCCCCUGGAGUCUGUAAAAGAGAUGCUUAAGUCAGUCAUGCAGGAACUCGAAGACUAUAGUGAAGGAGGUCCUCUCUAUAAAAAUGGUUCUUUGCGAAAUGCAGAUUCAGAAAUAAAACAUUCUACACCAUCUCCUACCAAAUAUUCACUAUCACCAAGUAAAAGUUACAAGUAUUCUCCCAAAACACCACCUCGAUGGGCAGAAGAUCAGAAUUCUUUACGGAAAAUGAUUUGCCAAGAAGUAAAGGCCAUUACGAAACUAAAUAGCAGUAAGUCAGCAUCCCGUCAUCGUUGGCCCACAGAGAAUUAUGGACCAGACUCGGUGCCUGAUGGAUAUCAGGGGUCACAGACAUUUCAUGGGGCUCCACUAACAGUUGCAACUACUGGCCCUUCAGUAUAUUAUAGUCAGUCACCAGCAUAUAAUUCCCAGUAUCUUCUCAGACCAGCAGCUAAUGUUACUCCCACAAAGGGUUCUUCUAAUACAGAAUUUAAGUCAACCAAAGAAGGAUUUUCCAUCGCUGUGUCUGCUGAUGGAUUUAAAUUUGGCAUUUCGGAACCAGGAAAUCAAGAAAAGAAAAGUGAAAAGCCUCUUGAAAAUGAUACUGGCUUCCAGGCUCAGGAUAUUAGUGGCCAGAAGAAUGGCCGUGGUGUGAUUUUUGGCCAAACAAGUAGCACUUUUACAUUUGCAGAUGUUGCAAAAUCAACUUCAGGAGAAGGAUUUCAGUUUGGCAAAAAAGACCCCAAUUUCAAGGGAUUUUCAGGUGCUGGAGAAAAAUUAUUCUCAUCACAAUGCGGUAAAAUGGCCAAUAAAGCAAACACUUCCGGUGACUUUGAGAAAGAUGAUGAUGCCUGUAAGACUGAGGACAGCGAUGACAUCCAUUUUGAACCAGUAGUUCAAAUGCCUGAAAAAGUAGAACUUGUAACAGGAGAAGAAGGUGAAAAAGUUCUGUAUUCACAGGGGGUAAAACUAUUUAGAUUUGAUGCUGAGAUAAGUCAGUGGAAAGAAAGGGGCUUGGGGAACUUAAAAAUUCUCAAAAAUGAGGUCAAUGGCAAACCAAGAAUGCUGAUGCGAAGAGACCAAGUACUAAAAGUGUGUGCUAAUCAUUGGAUAACAACUACAAUGAACCUGAAGCCCCUCUCUGGAUCAGAUAGAGCAUGGAUGUGGUUAGCCAGUGAUUUCUCUGAUGGUGAUGCCAAACUAGAGCGGUUGGCAGCACAAUUUAAAACACCAGAGCUGGCUGAAGAAUUCAAGCAGAAAUUUGAGGAAUGCCAGCGGCUUCUGUUAGACAUACCACUUCAAACUCCCCAUAAACUUGUAGAUACUGGCAGAGCUGCCAAGCUAAUACAGAGAGCUGAAGAAAUGAAGAGUGGACUGAAAGAUUUCAAAACGUUUUUGACAAAUGAUCAAACAAAAGUCACUGAGGAAGAAAAUAAGGGUUCAGGUACAGGUGCAGCCGGUGCCUCAGACACAACAAUAAAACCCAAUCCUGAAAACACUGGGCCCACAUUAGAAUGGGAUAACUAUGAUUUAAGGGAAGAUGCUUUGGAUGAUAAUGUUAGUAGUAGCUCAGUACAUGAUUCUCCGUUGGCAAGUAGCCCUGUGAGAAAAAAUAUUUUCCGCUUUGAUGAGUCAACAACAGGAUUUAACUUCAGUUUUAAAUCUGCUUUGAGUCUAUCUAAGUCUCCUGCCAAGUUGAAUCAGAGUGGGACUUCAGUUGGCACUGAUGAAGAAUCUGAUGUUACUCAAGAAGAAGAGAGAGAUGGACAGUACUUUGAACCUGUUGUUCCUUUACCUGAUCUAGUUGAAGUAUCCAGUGGUGAGGAAAAUGAACAAGUUGUUUUUAGUCACAGGGCAGAACUCUACAGAUAUGAUAAAGAUGUUGGUCAAUGGAAAGAAAGGGGCAUUGGUGAUAUAAAGAUUUUACAGAAUUAUGAUAAUAAGCAAGUUCGUAUAGUGAUGAGAAGGGACCAAGUAUUAAAACUUUGUGCCAAUCACAGAAUAACUCCAGACAUGAGUUUGCAAAAUAUGAAAGGGACAGAAAGAGUAUGGGUGUGGACUGCAUGUGAUUUUGCAGAUGGAGAAAGAAAAGUAGAGCAUUUAGCUGUUCGUUUUAAACUACAGGAUGUUGCAGACUCAUUUAAGAAAAUUUUUGAUGAAGCAAAAACAGCCCAGGAAAAAGAUUCUUUGAUAACACCUCAUGUUUCUCGGUCAAGCACUCCCAGAGAGUCACCAUGUGGCAAAAUUGCUGUAGCUGUAUUAGAAGAAACCACAAGAGAGAGGACAGAUGUUAUUCAGGGUGAUGAUGUAGCAGAUGCAGCUUCAGAAGUUGAAGUGUCUAGCACAUCUGAAACAACAACAAAAGCAGUGGUUUCUCCUCCAAAGUUUGUAUUUGGUUCAGAGUCUGUUAAAAGAAUUUUUAGUAGUGAAAAAUCAAACCCAUUUGCAUUUGGCAACAGUUCUGCCACUGGGUCUUUGUUUGGAUUUAGUUUUAAUGCACCUUUGAAAAGUAACGAUAGUGAAACUAGUUCAGUAGCCCAGAGUGGAUCUGAAAGCAAAGUGGAACCUAAAAAAUGUGAACUGUCAAAGAACUCUGAUAUCGAACAGUCUUCAGAUAGCAAAGUCAAAAAUCUCUCUGCUUCCUUUCCAAUGGAAGAAUCUUCAAUCAACUACACAUUUAAAACACCAGAAAAGGGAUUUAAUUUUAGCCUUUUUAAAUCUAAUCCCAUGGCCUUUUGGACUAGCACCCCUUCCUCACAGCCUGAGAGCAAAGGUAUAGAACUAGCAUUCUCAGUAUGAGAUAACAGCAGUUUUUAGCAGCUGGUAGCCCUUAGGAAAGUAUUAAUAACUGUGGCUGUAUGAAAUGAAGUACUUACCACUACAACAUGAAUGUUAAAGAAUGCCAGUUUAAGCAAAGUACCUUUUGACUGGUGGCAUGACACCCUUGUUGGUUUGUUUUUUAAAAUGUACUGGGAUGCUGAUUUGUAAUGUACUUCAUUGCUCUGCUAUUUCAGGUCUGCUCAGUGAAGACCUAUGUUUUAUCUAAUGUUUAUCUUUAGCCACUAACGUCUGCCAGUAUUCACAUGUAGUGGCAACGGCAUGUAUACAGUAUGGAAGAGUGUCCCUGUAGGGCUGUUCUUUUGUGCAUGGUUUAGAAAAAUGUUGUAUUUGAAAAUGGACCCCAUUUUUAACAGCCAGCAUUCUACAGCUUGCAUAUUAUAUAUGUUGCACAGAUCAUUUUUAGAAGUGUGGCUACUAGAGUGGAACAAGAAGUGGGAUCUGUUGAAGGCCUUCAAGAACAGGUUAGGGAAGUGAAACCUCACCCUUAGUGACCAGUAACACAUCUUAGCCAUGCCAAACAAGUACAAUGAUAAAAUAACAAUCUCUGAUUUUUUUUUGAGUAUACCAGUUUUAUUACCAGCUAAGGUAGCUCUUAAUCUUUUAUUUUAAAGAUACGGUCUUUGAGAAAUGUGAAAAGUGUUAACUUAAAAGUGGAUGUAUACUUGCGUACAGUUUCUGUGAGCUCUAGGUUAGGAAUCCCUGACCUAAGAACGAAUGUGCCUAUACACUACUGUAGAACAUAGAGCCUUAUUCUGUUUUGAAUCUGAUAAUGUCAUUGUCCCAAGGGACCUUAGAAAUGAAGACUUUAGACAUGAGUAAACUGAGGCCAAGAGAGGCUAUCUGAUUUACCCAAGAGGUCUUUACUGAGUAAUAGCAGAAGUGGAACAAGAAUCUGUAUCUUACGGUGUACUGUUAUUUCUCCUAGCUAGGAAAUGAUACUAGGUUUUCGUUUAUAAUGAAGGAGAGGGACAAAUUUAACAUUGUAAAAGGAAGGGCACUGGUUCUGCAGAGCAGUGUCAUCCAAUAGAAAUAAAAUAUAACCUGUGUAUGUAAUUUAAAAUUGUCAUUUGGUGCAAUGGCUUGUGCCUAUAAUCCCAGUUACUUGGGAGGCUGAGGCAGAGGGAUCACUUGAGCCCACAAGUUCCAGGCUUCAGUGAACUAUGAUCACAUCACUGCACUCCAGCUCUGGGUGACAAAGCAAGACCGCAUCUCAAAUAAAUACAUAAAUAAAUAAAUUUUCUAGUAGCCAUAUUAAAAAGAAUAAAAAGAAACAGUUAAAAAGGGAAACAGAUGAAAGUAACUUUAUCGAUAGAUUUGAUUUAACUCAUUAUGUCCAAAAUAUCAUUUUAACUUCUAAUUAAUAUAAAAAUUAAUGAUAUUUUACAUUAUUGUUUUUCACCAAGUCUUCAAAAUCCAGUGUGUGUGUUUACACUUACUGUUAGCAUGUCUUGAUUUGGACUAGCCACCUUGUGAGGUUUUAAUAGAAUGUGGCUAGGCUACCAUAUUGGACACCAUAGCUCUCAGAAUGUUUCCCUGUCACCAGUUGGUAUACAUGGCAUGCUUCAUAACUGGCUUACUUUAUUAAACUCCUUUAGCCAGAAGUUGUUCUUUACAUUAAUAGAUCAGAACAGGUUGCAUAUAGAAGUUUUUUCUGUUUCUAAUUUUUUGCCCUUUGCAUUGAUGGUGGCUGGGGAUGGGUUGUUUUCAGCCAUAUGAAUGGUCUUAGAUUUUAUAGUGUUAGCUACCCAUAGAGUAACAGUUUUUAUUUAAUUUUAUCUAGUAUCAUGCUUGAACACAGGCAAACUAGAUGCAACUCUAGUCACCUUCCAUUCUUGGCAAUUGUUAACUUUCCUUACAGGAACUAAUCACAGUUGGCUUUGGAUUAGUUUCAUAUGUAUACUAAUACUUGCUUAUGUUUUAAGAUUUUUUUCAAUUGCUGCAAAUG